CAUUUCUAUCAGCCUAUAGAUCUUGCAACCUGGAGAAACAAAAAUGUGUUUUGUCCUUAGCAUCCAGAAGGUAAUUGUACGAUGUAAAUGUUGUAUGCCUUCCUAGCUCUUGAUCUGGAAAUUGUCAUCAUUUCUAAAACAAAUAGAAAUAUACUUACUUUAAAAAUAAAUUAGUAUGUUUAAAACACAGAUAAUAAUUUAUCCCCAAAUUAUUAAGCAAUUACAAAUUCAAGCAGUUGGUGCUGAUUAAUUAUAUAUAUACAAGGUAGCAUUUUAAAAAUUUAUGAUAAAUUACAGCAAUCUGUUGAAGUGUUGAAGGUGAUUAUUUAUGAAGUGUGAUGUAAAUGAAAUUUGCCACAGUGCGGGGAAAAUAAAUUCUUUAUUAACAUCUAAUUAUCUUUUGCUCACUUAUGGAUUCAAUAUUUCCUACCUCUGUAUCAACUCUUAUGGCCUGGGGGCAGUAGUAUUUAUUAAGAUGGCAUUUUUAGUUCCAUCAUAAUUUAGCUUUAUUCAAAUUCCAGAUCAGUGCUAUCACAUUACUAUUUACUGAAAAAUUCUGAACUGUGUUGCCAAAAAAGGAUAAAAAGUAAGCUUUACAUUUCCUUCCCUGGGAGUCUCAUGACGCCGUUUUCUGUGUUUUCCUCAGUGAAUGGGUGGUCUUAUCACUGUUUGUUCAGUCAUCCUUCCAGACUGAACUGCUAGCUGUGCACAUCUUCCACACACAGAAAAUGUCUUGGAAGUUGAUUCUCUAGGUUUCUAAACUCAGCCUGUCUCUGUAUUUUUAUCGAUGUGUUAAAAAUAUUUGAGGAUCAUCCCAAGUGAAUCAGCUGAUUGACAGCUUUAGGGUCCAUAGAUUCUUAACAGAUGAAAUCUACCAAUAAAAAAUUUUCAAGGGCAAAUAAGAAGCCCUACAAUUGUGCUAAAUGCACUACCUACAAGAACAACAAGAACCAACUACUAUAGGUAUAACCAAUACUAUAGGUGUUUCAGAAGGCACAAAUUAGCAUAUUUACAUGGCUCAAAUUUUUAAUCAUAUUUUUAUUACUCAAUUUAUAUUAUUAUGAUACAGGAUGUGAUAACUUAGCUUCCUCUAACAGAUCCUGUCAUAUGCAUGUUUUUGCAUGCUACACUUUUGAAAAAAGCUUUUUAUCAUGAAAAAUUUCAAUCAUAGACAAAGGUAAAGAGAAUAGUAUAAUAAAACCCUUUGUACCCAGCUGCCAAUUUAAAAAGUUAUCCACGUGUUCUGUAAAUCUUUUCUCAUCUCUUUCCUUAUCCACUUCGCCCAUGCCCACCCCGGCCAGAGAUGAUUCUGAAGUCGAUCUCAGAUGUGUCUUUUUAUCUUUAACUAUUUUAGUUGAAUUCUAUACUUUUGAGGUCUAGCUAAUCAGAAAGAAGAGUGAAGAAAGAGACCAGGGCAGUCAGAGGAAUCAGAUGCCUUUUAUCUGAGAAAUGAGAGAAGGAAUACUCUCUUUCAGAAACACUGGUCUAGAAGACCCAGGAGGAAGAUUUCAGGGUCUGUAAAUAAGAAAAGCACAAUAAUGUGGAAACCAGUUAAGAAUUUAUCUCUGUGUCAUUAAGGCAUAGACCCAGAACUAAAGAGUACAAGGUAUGGGGUGAUUGAUGUCACUCAGUUUAAGGAAGAACUUCCUAAAGUAAAGUGGACCAAAGAUUCAAUGAACUGUCACAAGGAAUUGAUGGUUUCAGCUCAGCAGAGUUUUCAAGUGGAUCGGGCAACAGCUUGAUAGCGCGAUAUAGAGGCAAAGUACAGGAGAUUCAGAUGAGAUUUUAUGUUGUGAGUUUUUCCAAACCCAGAAGCCUGCAAAGUGUGGCGGGCUUCUCAGCUGAAAUUCUUCCUGGCUCAUAUAUUAAAUAAGAAUCUAAUCUUUUCUGAAUGUGAACAUCAGGUAAGAGCCUCAUCCUGCUGUUUGCAAUGUGGACUCAGAGAGCUGUUCGAAGGUUUUGAGCCAGCAACCUAGAAAUCCACCUUGAUUCUGCUACUUUCUAGCUGGGCAGAGCUCUGUAAGGUAUAUCACGUCUUCACUGAAUCUCAGGCUUCUAAUCUGUACAAUGGGAUUUUAAGGGAGUCUUCUGAGAAUUAAAUUAGGUGCAUACUUAAAAUCUCUCUCCUUCAUUUUGUACCUAGUUAGGUAUUUUGUAUUAGGUGUUCAUAUUUACUCUUCCAAUAUCCAGAGCUUGCUGAACUUUCCAUAUUGAUACUGCUUUGGUAAAGUUGAGUUUGUAUUGAUUUAUUCAGCAGUCUGAACUUGGGGUUCAGUAGUGAGUUACACAGGGUCUGGCCACAAGUUGGCUAGAGUUUCAUGGGCUUUCUGAGCUGGACAAGUUACCUUUAUUACUGUAGGAUAAAUAAGUUAAUCAUGCUUACUUUGUCCCAUCAAAAGAGAAUAGUUAUAAUUAUUUCAUUGCUAUAAUCUUCCUACAUUCUUUCUCAUGAGGGUGAGAAGAAGUUGCUUAGAAGAUAAAAUAUUGUUUUCUAACACUAUCUUACGGGACCAGAUAAAAGUUUCUAAUUUAGCCUGAAAUUACAUUAAAUAAUAAUGGUGUAUUCAACUUAGCAUUUUAUCAUUAGAUUGAUAGAGACUUUUAAAAUGUGUAGUAUCUCGUCAUUUAAGGAGCCAUGGCCCUCUAAAGAUUGUCACGAAUAACAGGAAACCCUCCAGAUCAUUUAUUUCCAUUCAUUCUCAUUAAUAAUAGUAUUUAAAAGCAGAAGUUUGCCAGAAGACUCUAUUUAUAAGAUACUUAGCACAGAAGCUCACUUGUGCUUUAAAAUGUGCCCUGGAUAACUCUGGCAUCUUGUGUUAUCUGAUAUAUCAAACUAAAACACAGAACCAUGGAUAGACUGUUCUCUCCUUUGGAAACAUCAACCUGUAUUCAGAGACUCGAACCAUUCCCUGCUCUCCUAAAAUGCCCUCAAGGCAGACGUAGCACCAGCAGUAUUUGGAGCUCAUACAGUGCGGCAUUGAGGACGGAUGCCUUUUGUUCACAAACAGAUUGGGAAAUGUGAGAUAAAUGGAUUUUUUCGCGGUAAGUGGGAGAAAAUGUGGGAGAGAUUUGGAAGCAGGGCAGCCGUGGGGCAAGGAAUGUUGAAAUGUAGCAAUUACUCUUUGGUCUUCCUCCGCAAAACACUGCCCUUCUCCGCCUAGCAUUUUUCAGAUGCCAGGCCCUGAACAUGAAAACACGGUGUGCCUGCUGAGCCCUUAACAUUCUCAAGAGCGCCUGCUGGAGAGCCAGCCAGGGCUUGCUGAAUCCUGUGUCUGGAACCCAGACUUGCAGGGUAGGGAGAAAGCAGCCUUGCAGUGGCCUAAACAGACGCUAAGUGGACAGCUCACUUGAACUUGGUUUAGCAGACCUCAGAAGUUGCUUGUUUUAAUUUCCUUUUGUUUGUCUUAUUCGUGAGGGAGGGAUCCCUUGCCCUAGAGUUAUGGGGAUAGCUGAACAUGGGACGCCAGGCACUGGACAGAUGAGAUCAGCAGCAGUUUAUGAGUCACAUAUACUCACAGCCUGGAGCAGGAGGACCGCACACACCACACAAAGCCACAUGGGAGUCCCGCGGCAGAAGAGUUGAACAUCACAGGGCUGUGGGAGGCAGGCCUUACAGUGGAAGGAAGGCUGUGGAAUGGGAGUGUGAUGAAGCUACCAAAAAGGCCUGUUACAGCAAAGGCAAAUCAAAGGAGGAAUGUCAGAACUACAUCCGGGUGCUUCUGGUGGGUGGCGACCGGUUAUUCACCUGUGGGACCAAUGCAUUCACGCCUGUCUGCACCAACCGCUCGUUGAGCAACCUGACUGAGAUCCAUGAUCAGAUCAGUGGCAUGGCCCGCUGUCCCUACAGUCCCCAGCACAAUUCCACAGCGCUCCUCACAGCUGGUGGGGAGCUCUAUGCUGCUACAGCCAUGGAUUUUCCAGGACGUGAUCCUGCCAUUUACCGAAGCCUAGGCAUUUUACCUCCUCUCCGCACGGCGCAGUACAACUCCAAAUGGCUCAAUGAGCCAAACUUUGUGUCAUCUUAUGACAUCGGAAAUUUUACCUACUUCUUUUUCCGAGAAAAUGCAGUAGAGCAUGACUGUGGGAAAACAGUGUUCUCCAGAGCUGCCCGGGUGUGCAAGAACGAUAUUGGUGGGCGCUUCCUGCUGGAAGACACCUGGACCACAUUCAUGAAGGCUCGCCUGAACUGCUCCCGUCCUGGGGAAGUCCCCUUUUACUACAACGAAUUGCAGAGUACUUUCUUCCUGCCUGAGCUGGAUUUGAUCUAUGGCAUCUUUACCACCAAUGUGAACAGCAUUGCGGCCUCAGCUGUGUGCGUCUUCAACCUGAGCGCCAUCGCGCAGGCCUUCUCUGGGCCCUUCAAGUACCAAGAAAACUCGCGCUCGGCCUGGCUACCGUAUCCCAACCCAAACCCCCACUUCCAGUGUGGCACCGUGGACCAGGGCCUGUACGUGAACCUGACCGAGAGAAAUCUGCAGGAUGCUCAGAAGUUCAUUCUGAUGCAUGAGGUGGUACAGCCAGUGACCACAGUGCCCUCCUUCAUGGAGGACAAUAGCCGCUUUUCCCACGUGGCAGUCGACGUGGUGCAGGGCAGAGAAGCGCUCGUCCACAUCAUCUAUUUGGCCACAGAUUACGGAACCAUUAAGAAAGUGCGGGUACCCCUGAAUCAGACCUCAAGCAGCUGUUUGCUGGAAGAGAUUGAGCUCUUCCCUGAGAGGCGGAGGGAGCCCAUCAGGAGCCUGCAGAUCCUGCACAGCCAGAGUGUCCUGUUCGUGGGCCUGCGGGAGCACGUGGUCAAGAUCCCCCUGAAGAGGUGCCAGUUCUACCGCACACGCAGCACCUGCAUUGGGGCCCAGGACCCUUACUGUGGCUGGGAUGUGGUAAUGAAGAAAUGCACAAGCCUGGAGGAGAGCCUGAGCAUGACGCAGUGGGAACAGAGCAUCUCUGCGUGUCCGACCAGGAAUCUCACCGUGGAUGGGCACUUUGGUGUGUGGUCUCCGUGGACGCCUUGCACGCACACAGAUGGCAGCGCCGUGGGAUCCUGCCUCUGUCGAACCCGCUCCUGCGACAGCCCGGCCCCGCAGUGUGGUGGCUGGCAGUGCGAGGGCCCUGGCAUGGAGAUCGCCAACUGUUCCAGGAACGGAGGCUGGACUCCCUGGACCUCGUGGUCUCCCUGCAGCACUACCUGUGGGAUCGGCUUCCAGGUGCGGCAGCGCUCCUGCAGCAACCCCACUCCCAGGCACGGGGGCCGGGUGUGCGUGGGACAGAACCGCGAGGAAAGAUACUGCAAUGAACAUUUGCUAUGUCCCCCACACAUGUUCUGGACAGGCUGGGGUCCUUGGGAACGGUGCACAGCCCAAUGCGGGGGUGGCAUUCAAGCUCGCCGCAGGAUCUGUGAGAAUGGGCCUGACUGUGCAGGCUGCAAUGUGGAGUACCAGUCUUGCAACACCAACCCGUGUCCUGAGCUGAAGAAGACCACGCCCUGGACACCCUGGACACCUGUCAACAUCUCUGACAACGGCGGCCACUAUGAGCAACGAUUCCGAUACACAUGCAAAGCCCGCCUGGCUGAUCCGAAUUUGCUGGAAGUGGGAAGACAGAGAAUCGAAAUGCGGUACUGUUCUAGCGACGGCACCAGUGGCUGCUCCACAGAUGGGCUUUCUGGGGAUUUCCUGCGUGCUGGGAGAUACUCUGCCCACACGGUCAACGGGGCUUGGUCAGCCUGGACGUCGUGGUCACAGUGCAGCCGUGACUGCAGCAGGGGCAUUCGGAACCGGAAGCGUGUUUGCAACAACCCCGAACCCAAGUAUGGGGGAAUGCCUUGCCUUGGCCCAUCUCUGGAAUACCAGGAAUGCAACAUUUUGCCCUGCCCAGUGGAUGGCGUGUGGUCUUGCUGGUCCCCCUGGACAAAAUGUUCAGCAACAUGCGGCGGUGGACACUAUAUGAGGACCCGCUCUUGCUCCAAUCCAGCCCCGGCCUAUGGAGGGGACAUCUGCCUGGGGCUGCACACAGAAGAGGCACUCUGCAACACGCAGCCCUGCCCAGAGAGCUGGUCGGAGUGGUCGGACUGGUCUGAGUGUGAAGCCUCUGGCGUCCAAGUCCGCGCCCGCCAGUGCAUCCUCCUGUUCCCCAUGGGCAGCCAGUGCUCCGGGAACACCACGGAGAGCCGGCCGUGUGUGUUUGACUCUAAUUUCAUCCCAGAAGUAUCUGUGGCAAGAUCCAGUAGCGUAGAAGAGAAAAGGUGUGGAGAGUUCAACAUGUUCCACAUGAUCGCCGUGGGGCUGAGCAGCUCCAUCCUCGGCUGCCUCCUCACCCUGCUCGUCUAUACUUACUGCCAGCGGUACCAGCAGCAAUCCCACGAUGCGACUGUCAUCCACCCCGUCUCACCUGCCCCCCUUAAUACCAGCAUAACCAACCACAUCAACAAACUGGACAAGUACGACUCGGUGGAGGCCAUCAAGGCAUUUAACAAAAACAACUUGAUCCUAGAGGAAAGAAACAAAUACUUCAACCCACAUCUCACUGGGAAGACCUAUUCUAAUGCCUACUUUACAGAUCUCAAUAAUUAUGAUGAGUACUAACAGCUUUCAUGUUUUUGGCUUCUUGUAAAUCCCCAGUUCCUCAAGGCCUGUGCCCCAUGACUGCCCAUGUUUCUGAGGCUUCAGAGUCGAAGUUUGGAUACAUUUCAAGUGCAUUUCAAGCCACCAGAGUGUCCCAUUGCUGCCAAAAAUACACGUCUUUAAAAGCAACAAAAAUUGAAAUAAGACAUCGUGAAAAUCUUGACCAUUGUUGAAUGAGCCAGGGUGUGAAGUUUUUAAUUGUGUUCAUCCUAUUUUUCUGACAAGUCCAUUGGUUUGUUUUUUGAGCAUUAUUUUAUAAAUGUGCCACCCACAUUGGAAGGAGUCUUUCUUUAGAACUUUGGAGUGUAAAUCUUCAUGAUGUUGUAAUUCAAGAAAAUAGGCACUUUCUCUGAAAGACCUGCUCCUUCCACAAGAAGUGCAUAGGUCCAUAAUAUUUCAUAAAAUGAAGAAAAAGAAUGUGGCCAAACAAUUAUUCACCAUGGAUUGCCCAACUUUCCAAAUCUGGAUAAAGCUGUGGGAUUCUUGGAAGCAGCUUGAGUGUUUUCAUCUUGCCUGGGAAGCCCAGGAAUUCCACCUGGUCCACACCGGCAGAAGUUACAGUAGACUGUGAGGCACCCCACCUUGCUCCUGAUGCAGUUUCUGUGCCAUUGCUGGUGCUGGUGGAGGCAGCGGAGCAGAGGCUCAGGCACAAUGAAGCGUGGAUGUGUUCUGCAGGUUGCUGCAAAACUCACCUUAUUCUGACUUUUGGAUUUCAUGGCAUUCCAGGAAGCUCCUUGCCAUGCUGUUGGCCUGGAAGUCCACCUGUCUGGUCCAUAGUGACGUCCUGAAGAGCCAGUCUGUAAAAUAACCAACCACUUACUUAGCGUUUGGAUAGACUCCAUGCCUUCUCUCUCCCUGCAAAGAAAAAUCUUGAACAUUUAUGAUGUCAAUUAGUGAAAGUAUUGAAAAUACUAAAUUAUAACUAAAAGCAACUUUUUAUGUUAUUGAAAAUAUUGAAAGAACUGAUAUUAAUGAUAAUCAUUUUAUUUUUCAUCUCUCUGAUAUACCCAAUGUGUGGCAAUCAGCCCCUACCACGAGCAUUAAUACCAUGUAAAGCUGGCUUUCUGGAGUCUGCCAGGUCCACACGAAGUGCUACCCCCAGUUUCUGCUGUUACUUGCUGCCUCCAGGCCAGGGGAGCAGGAGAUGCUCAGCUCUGGUGCCUUUUCUUUUAUUUCAGUGCUGCCUUCCCACCCACCCAGUCCAUUCACCCUCACCUCUCCCUGCAUGGAGGCAACAGCAUUUCAAGAUGUACCUUGGGAAGUCAGGAUAGCUGGAAGUAAGGGUUUUUGGGAUCCCUGUGGUCUCUUCACUGAUCAUCGAUAAGCAUUUAAGAGUGUGCUAACACCAUUCACAGAGGUCCCUGGAAAAAAAUAUAUAAUUUUCUCACAAACAACCAAUACAUAACCUAUGGCAGUUGGUUGAAUAAUUAUUGAAAAAAAGAACACGACUGAAAAAGUUCAUCUGAUGCCUCUGAGCAUGUGAUAAAGUCCUGGGUAGACACGGAAACGUGUUCUUACAAAUGAACCUUCGGAUCUAUGAAAGAAAAUAUAGUAGGGGGACUAAGGAACAUAGAAUUUUAUUAGCAUAUGUGAUUUUACCCUUAUCUUUGUUUCUAAUUUAAAGAAACAAUUUCAGAAAGUGUUAGAAGAAUUCUAUGUUUAAUAAUGAAUAUUGUUGAGUUCAAAAUAUUCUCAUAUACCCAGAUUUACAGAGAUGACACAGUAUUGAAAUGGCAGGUGGGCUCUGUAAGUUAUUUUGGAUUAAUGACAUUCAGGGUCUUUGCAGUGGGGACUUCAUGUUGCCUCUCACUCAUUCCUCAUAUGUCAGAGUCUUCUGUCUAUAUGCACAUGCUCAAAGUCCAUACUCAGUAGGGGAAAUCUAGCCGGAUGGUUCUCCAAUUGUUCCUCGGCUGGAUUUUCAUCAUCAGAUAUUUCAACUCAUCUCAUCAGUUUCUUGUAAGAAAAAAACAUUUUCACUUUGUAGCACAUUUUAGUUAUUUUUGAGUCUUCUUCCCUAAUAGUUUGUAAGCUUAAAGGGACAUUUUAUUUUCCCUGGUAAAGAGGAUUCUAAUAUUUCAAGAAUGUUUCACUGGAAUUGAUGGGAAAUGGUUUCUAAAUGGCAUCGAAGCUGGUCUUUAAUGAGUCUUUUGCAAUGACUUGGGAAAAACACCCUCCCUCACUACAGGAUCUUCAUGUUGUUAAUAAUAUAAACAAACCUUUGAAAUUAGCAUUGCAAAAGAAUCCCAUUUUUGUUUCGUACCACACUGUUCAAAGGAAAAUUGUUUAUCUCUCUUCCUUUCUCUCUCUCUCUUAUUUGACAGAAUAGCAAGUGUUUAGAUAAUUUCAGAUAUAUUCUAAGUAUUUUACCAGCUGUGGAAUAAGUUGUGUUUGUCCAUCACUGUGUAGCUACCGUUCACAUGUUCUGGCUCUGUACUCCACGCUUAUCGCGUGAACCCUCACAUGUUGGACUUUCACAGUGUGAUCUCUCACCUGUCUUGGAAACUCCUUCAUAAAGCCGCUCUUCCUUAGGCCUGGGCUGUUUGGAAGUCCUGGUGAAACUUUGCGGUUCACAUUUUAAAUUCCUGAAUGACCUUUUCAUUCUCUCUUUCUUUAUCUUUGUUUUUGUCCUUCAUUCCCUCCUUUUGUUCUUCCUUCCUGCCUUCUUUUCUUCUUUCCUUUCUUCUUUCUUUAAUUCUUCCUUUCUUCCUAUUUUCUUGGUACAAGUGGAACAAAAACCAACACAUAGUUUUAAGCUACACCUUUCUGCACCUGAUGUAAAAUGACAUUAAUCACUAUUUAACUUCUAAAAUUAUUUCUGAAUACAGUUGGAGAUAGGCUGGUUUUCAUGAGGAAGCUGGCUUGGCUUUAGUCUUACAUUUAAAUUCUUUGAAAGUGGCUCCCAGUGCUAUUCAGGGUCCUUUCUUGAGGCCAGACUCAUCACCAUCUACUAUUGAUUUUACAGUGCACUGACAGUUUACAGGAAGGAGAAGAACAGAAUUUCUGCACACUACACAACAUGUGGGCUUCCUGUAGCUCCAGGGACAUGUAGCUUUGGUGAAACUGGGGUUUUGUAACCUCUGAAUGAUAUGGACUUAGUGAAUUCUAAGGAACUCAGGGGGCACGUGGUCAGGCUCCACCGCACAGAAGAGCCACAGUCUCCAGACUCAUGGCGUUCCCUCCAGAACUCCCCAUUCCCCUCUGAGCAUAUUUCUAUGCUGCUGCUUCUUGUGACUUACAUGAGGCAUCUCAGCUUCUUCAUGUUUGUAGGGAUGGUUCCCUAAGCCUGUUCAAGUAGGCUCUCACUAGAGUUACCAUUCAUAUUUGAGAAGAAAAGAACAUUUAAUAAAUGUAUGUGUGGGGCUGAGGUUCUAAAGGAAUUGAAAAGAGACGAUAAACAUUGAAUGAGGGUGAGGGCAUCCCUGCUGGGGAGAAACCUCUGUCCCUAGGAAGAGUCCGUUCAUGUCAUGUGGUUUGGGAUGAACCAGGGGUCUGGCCCCAUCGGGUCACAGGUGAUGGCAAAUAGAAAAGAAGCAAAUGGAGGAAAUAGUCGGAUAAGUAGGUGACGUGAAAGGCAGGACCUGGUCACCCCAGCAAGUGCUAUGGACAGUUCCCGGAAACGGUUGCCCACUUCACAGGUCCAUGGGUCUGACCCUUGGACUCUGCCAGGAUCAACUGCCCAGAGUGCCAGAGUUUUAGCCAAAGGUGUACUUACUUCCUUAUUUAUCUGCAAAAGGAUGGAAACUGUGGGAGUCAAAGCCUAUUUUGCUGAGUGUUCCCACUGGAGUCUCUGGUAGAAUUAGCAGGUCAUGCUGUCAAAAUCAUGGACAAAGGCUGGGUGCAGUGGCUCAUGCCUAUAAUCCCAGCACUUUGGGAGGCCAAGGUGGGCGGAUCACCUGAGCUCAGGAGUUUGAGACCAGCCUGGGCAACAUGGGGAAACUCCAUCUCUACAAAAUAUACAAAAUAUUAGCCAGCCAUCGUGGUGCGUGCCUGUGGUCCCAGUUUCUUGGGAGGCUGAGGCGGGAGUAUCAUUUGAGCCAGGAGGUUGAGGUUGCAGUGAGCUGAGAUCACAUCACUGCACUCCAUCCUGGGUGACAGAGAGAGACCCUGUCUCAAAAAAAAAAAAAAAGAACAAAGUCUUAGCGGGGGGUCUCUAUGUCCCCAAGUGGCUCUCUAAGGGGAUCCAUUAGCGUAUAAUUGAAUAUCAAAGGGAAUUUUACCUUAAACAUAUAUCAAGUCUAUACUCAGCUAAUCGUUUUGUCUAAACACAGCCUUGUUAGCAUUUGAAUUUACAAAUAUUCAUUUGCUUAUUUGCAGUGUUCCUUUUGCUUUUAGAAUAAAUCAUAAAUAUUUCCCCAAUACUGUCAAGAUACUUCUUCAACUUUGUCCCUGAACCAUCAGCUUUCUUUAGGGUCCGGGUAUCCUUUACACUUCAAUGGGGUUUUCUUGUGUGUGUCAUUGGGGGUAACUCCAUUGACCUCAGCAUUUCUAUCUCAAGAGAUGGCUCUGGAACACAGAACCAGAGGCAACAGGUACUAAUGGUUGAUAAAAUUAACAGCGACUGCAUAACCAUUUUCCACAUGGCAGGGCUGUGCUUAAGCCCCACACCUCCAAUAAUCAAUUUCUAUGACGGUACUAAUAACCUUAACUAUAUGCAAAUUCUUCACCACUUAUGAUAUGGUACAAACUGGAGUUUACAGAUGGCCUUGGCCUUGCCUAGCCCAUUUGUUCAUCCUAACUUCUUCAUCACUUCCUGAUGCACUUGGGGAAGCAUGUUGACACAACGUUACCAAUAUUUGAUUACCUAUGGUUAUCUGCAAUUACCUACGCUUAUCUUAUCAGACCCUAGAUGCCAUUUGAGCCCCUUACUUCUUUGGGCAGUGGGUGAAAUGGGAGAACAUAGAGAAAUGUUCACUUUGACCUAAGAAACGCAUAAAAGGGAAUGCCAUGCACAAUGUAAGAUAAAAUGUUUGGGGACAGGGGAUCAUCGUGAAAUUUAUUUCUGCUAUUCUGCCCUAUUGAGGUCAUUAAUUAUAAUGGAUUUAAAGAUUUUUUUUUAAACUCUACAAACACUAAGCCAAGGAAUUCAGGUUAUCUGCUAUGUUAACCUAAUAAAGCAAAGGAAAAUAAGUUGCUUUAAUCCUUGCUUGUUAACCUAAUAAAGCAAAGGAAAAUAUGUUGCUUUAAUCCUUGCUUCUUUUCUCUUUUGGUAAUAGAAAAGGUAAAUAAGAUGUAAUGUUGAACUGCUGGUGAUGAUUUCUAAAACGACUCUUUAAAUACUCCUUUCCUAUGGACUUAUAUUAAAGAUGCAUUGUACACAUUGUUUUAGCAGAUAGAUCAAAGAUAUACUCAGUGGUCAUCUGUUGCAUUAUCAGAAAUUUGAUACAUGUUACAGAAGCAUGAGGAAGGGAAUCCUAUCCACUUUUGAAAAUAGAGUUCACAUUGCAAGCGACAUAGGGCAUUAUCAAAACCAAUUCAGAGCCUGGCACAAAAUGUAUACUUCCUAGUGAAAGCUGUCUCAAAACACAGCCUUUUUGAUGGAUCAUAUUAGCUCAUAUCUGCCAUAGAAAGGCAAUCAAGCUUACUCCCUGCAAUCGGAGUCAAUAUCAAUUCUUGCUCAAGCAAACAUGUUUUACAGUGUUGGCGCAAUGGCAGGAACUAGUCAAGGGCACUUUCAGAUCUGGAAAGAGGAAAGAGGAGGUAGAAAAUCACUCUUUUGUGUUUCUUAAACUGUCAAUCAAGCAAGAAAAUUUAUUCCACCCCUUCAUAUUUGCUCUAAAAUCUGGGGCCAGUAGUUGAAAUGUGAUCUUGUUCUUUCUCAGCCUUUUGGCAAUUUAAUGCCAAAUAUUCCAAAUGUUAGAUGAAUGGCAGUAAUAAAAUGAUUCAAAUGUUUGAUAAAUACAAGCUGAGAGCAAAAUCUGGACUCUGAAAAAUCGGAACUAUUUUAUCAUGUUGCUAAAAUGAGAGCAUCAUUUUCUUCCCUCUCUGUAAGUGCGGUAGUUUAAUUUCCUAGAAAAAGUUGCUAGUGCCUUGUUUAAGAUGAUCAUUUAUCAUUUCAUGUGGAUAUUAUUGGUCUAAUUAGAAGGAGAAGAUUGAUUGGAUUUACUUUAAAGAAAAUUAUUCUCCUAUGUCUCUUUGAACUCAGGAAUAGAAAAUGACCAAGAAGCACAUCAUCUUCAGAUGUGAUUUUUGCCCUCACUGGGGAUGUAGAACCAGAAUAGGUACAACAUAUGCUCAGAAGAGAGGUGACUUCAGUAUUAGCCUUCUAGAAACUAACAUCACUUUAAUUUUUACAUGUUCCAAAAAAAAUCAUAGUGAUUGUUCUGUAAUAAGAAUGUUAACGUGAUGCCUAUAGAAGUUAGAGGUUUUUGUUUCUGUUUCUCUUCAGGCAAGUCCAUAGAUAGAGGAAAAUCAGACACAGGCUGGUGACAACUGGUAUAGAUACAGUGAGCAUGGAAUGAGAACCACCUACAACAUUGCCUGAUUAUUUUUAAGUUUAUAUCAAAACUGCUUCACAAGUUCACAAAAGUUGUCACUCUUAAUUUGGGUUAAGAAAAGUAAUAGUAUUAUCUCUGCUGAAGUUGAUUGUUUUUCUCUUUUACCAUGACUGUUGGCCAAAAGCAAGCUGAACCUCUGCACUUUGAAACAAAGCACAGUAUGAAUCUUUAACCCAAGCACUUAGUUUCACCACUGAGAUUCUACAUCAUCUGCAAGAAAAUGCACAAACUUUUGGUCCAAUGUUGGAUUCUUCAAAAGUGCAUAGCAAAACUUUUGUGCUAUGCCGCUUGAUGUAACUUUUAAAGAUGUUAUCAAAUGUUAAAUGCCUCAUUCUGCGUUAAUUUGCUGUUGGCUGUUUUGUGAACACAAAAUAAACUUGAGAUUUUUUUUUUUUUUUUUUUUUGUGAAACUCCUCCAAAGCCAAUUUCAGCCCUUGGUAAGCUUGCAGACAGUUACUGAUCUUAAAUUUAAUUUUAAAAGACAAUGUAUCUUAAUUAUAAUUUAGCUUUUUAAAACAAUGAGAUAGCUUUACAUUUCCCCUUUGUUUGAAUGAGAAAAUGGAUCUUGGGUUGCUAUGCUAGAACACUUGUAGAUUGCUGGGUCCUUUGUAAGGGGGCCAUGGACACACCACACUUUCUUUCAAUCCUUACAUUUGAAGCAUUGAUAUUCUUCAAAACCUUCUUGUUACAUGUGCGCAAUAGAAAUUUCUAAUGUUCAUGACUUUUAUCUUUCCUGUCCAUCAAUUCACUGGUUGUAAAUGCUUCCUGAGAGCUGUCUAGGUCUGUAUCCCAGAUUGUUGCUUAAUGACAUCUGACAGAUGCAUUGUUUUCUGAAAUCAGCUUAAGACACCAAUUGUGGCAACUGGAAACUCAUUACCUGCUGCAUUGGAUCAACUAUGGAAGUUGGAGCAGGGGUGGGCGGAGGUCACCUAACCAAUCAAUGGAAGGCAACUCACACCUGCUCCAAGCCUCAGCUUUGAGAAACAAACACGUUUAUAAGAAAAAAUAUAUAGCUAUUAUUACAGAAGUGAAUAUGUUGUGCUCUCUUACUGCUCUUGGUGCAUUGACAGUUUCUGUAUCUCAACCCUAUUCAUCUUUAUGAAAAAGCAUUCUGAAGAUCUAUCCUCAGCACUGCUGAGUGUGCAGUCACACUUUCCUACCAACCCCCUUCUUACCAUCUCUAGCUGCCAUUUGUGGGGGGAACAAAACAAGGGAAUCCUGAUUGUGUACAGUAUAAAUUGUAUUAUAUUUUUUGUACUUAUGUUUUAUGUAAAUAGUUUGUCUCAUUCAAUUGUAUGUGAGCAUUGAAAUAAAUCCUACCAUUUAGGGGA